AACCAUAGCGGCUCGCGUGGGUCGGCUGGCAAGUAACCAUAGCGGCGAGCGUGGGGCGGAGUGUGGCUCGGUAGUCCUCUGCGUGCCCUCCUGGGAGCUGGGUGCUGUGAGUCCUCCCCUAGCGGGCUGGUCUCGGCGCGGAGUCGGCGCCGAACCCGAGCUGCUGCUCUGGGGCGUGUGCCUAGGGCGCAGGGCUGGAGCGCGGGGGCUGCGCGGUUGCUCGCGGCUCCGCUGAGGUCUCUAGGAAAGGGGGCGAUUUGAGGGUUCCGCCGUGACCGCUUCCAACGGCGGACACGCGCGCUCUGGACCAGAGCCGUUGCCCGCUGUCUCGUCACCCGAAGCCUCCUCCUGACGCCGUGCUAGUGCGAGGGUCUCCAGGGGAAUUCGGGGCACAAGUCGGGCCGGAGCAUCCGGGCGGCCGCUUGAGAUCGGCGCUUUGAGAACUGAGCGCAUGUGGAGUUCGGAGGAAAAGGGCUCAGUUGUGGAAGCUGAUCGAGGAAGCCUAAGCAGGCUCUGUGAAGUGGGAAUAGUGGUAUUUGAGUCAAGGUUUGCUUAACUGGAAAGCCCGUGAGAAGAAUGGAGCAGUUGAGAAUGUGGAAGCUCCAGAGUUUUCGGCAAUUUCUCUUCUUUUUUCUUGGGAUGAGGAGAGGUGAAUAAAUAGAUUGAAGAUGGAAAAUCCCCAAGACAUUUUCUCAAGUAAUGGUGGCUGUCUAAGUGAUAUAGUUAUAGAAAAAUACCUGGUUGAAUCCAAGGAGUCUGUGUCUCAUGUUCAGCUUGCUUGCAGCAUGCAGGACUGUGCUUUCCCUUUGGAUGGAACUGAACUUUGUAUAUGGAACACUAAGGAUCCUUCUCAUCAGCUUCUAAUCCUACGAGGACACCAUCAGCCAAUUACUGCUAUGGCUUUUGGAAAUAAAGUGAACCCACUUCUAAUCUGCUCAGCAUCACUGGAUUAUGUUAUAAUGUGGAACCUGGAUGAAUGUAGAGAGAAAGUACUUCAAGGGCUGGUCCCUCGAGGGACUGUCAUGGGCUCGCUUUUGGGAAAGGUGCUGUGUUUACAGUUGAGCCUGGAUGAUCAUGUUGUUGCCGUGUGUGCUGGAAACAAAAUAUUCAUGCUGGAUAUUGAGCAGCGAUUUUCUGUGACAUACAUAGAACGUCCUGAUGUUAAUAACCGCCACAAAGUCCCACCACCGACCUUCCUGCACACAUUCUCUCAGACUCAGGCUGUUCGGGCCGAGCUGCAGGGCCACCUGGGCCCGGUGACUGCGGUGGAGUUCUGUCCCUGGCGAGCAGGCACCCUCAUCUCGGCGUCUGAGGACAGAGGCUUUAAGGUCUGGGACCAUUGUACAGGAUCAUUAAUAUACAGUUCAUCUGUGUUAUCAGCAUAUCCUCUUCUCAGUUUAUUCAUUGAUGCAGAAAGCAGGCAGCUGGUCACCGGGUGUGCUGACGGCCAGCUUUGGAUCUUCAGUUUGAUGGAUGGACACCAUUAUCGUCGUGUGGCACGGGUUGACCUAAGGAAGAAGACAGAGACUUUCUCCACAAGAAGGGUUAAGUCUGGGCUGUGCAGCCAGCCAGAAGAAAGCCAGCUUCCCUCUACAAGUGCUCUGGGAAAAGGAGAGCAGGUUGAAGUAACAUUUCCUGUACUGAGACUUGCACCCUGUGAUCUCUCACUCAUCCCAAAUUCUGCAUGUGGAUGUCUUUCUUCUGAGAACACCCGAUGUGUGUGGAUCGGAAGCUCAGUGGGCUUAUUCGUAUUUAACCUGGCAAACCUGGAAGUGGAAGCUGCUUUGUAUUACAAGGAUUUCCAGAGCCUCAGCAUCCUGCUGGCCGGAUCGUGUGCCCUGAGGAACCGCACUGCGGAUCAAAAGGUGCUGUGCUUGCUGGCCUCCCUCUUUGGCGGGAAGAUUGCCGUGUUGGAGAUCAACCCGGCCGCGCUAGUCAGGGCUCAGCAGUGCCCCAGCAUGGGGCAGAGCCUCUCGGUGCCAGCCAGCUCCUGUGUCCUACCGACCUCUCCACUGUAUCUGGGAAUUGCCAAGGAGAAGAGUACCAAGGCUGCUAGUGAACAGCGACGUGCUGCACGGAACGUCAUGAAGGACCAACGCCUGGUUUUCCAUAGUAAAGUUAGGUCAUCUGGUUAUGCGUCAGCACCACAUGUAACUAUGUUUUCACCAAAGACCAACAUCAAGAGUGAGGGGAAAGGAUCUUCAAGGAGCAGGAGCAGCUGCGCACGGGAGGCAUACCCCGUGGAGUGCGCUGUGCCCACCAAGCCCGGCCCCCAGGUCGCUGCCGCCCCCACCUGCACACGUGUAUGCUGCAUCCAGUACUCAGGAGAUGGGCAGUGGCUGGCCUGUGGGUUGGCCAACCAUCUGUUACUCGUUUUUGAUGCCAGCCUGACUGGGACACCUGCUGUGUUUUCAGGUCACGACGGGGCAGUGAAUGCCGUGUGCUGGAGCCAGGACCGGAGGUGGCUGCUCUCUGCGGCCCGGGACGGGACCCUGCGAAUGUGGUCGGCUCGUGGGGCAGAGCUCGCACUGCUUCUGGGCAAAGACAUGUUUUCUAAACCUAUACAGUCUGCACAGUUCUAUUAUAUAGAUGCCUUUAUAUUGUUAUCUUCUGGCCCUGAAUUUCAGCUACUGAGGUAUCACAUUGACACUUGCAAAGAUGAGAUUAAGAGAUAUAAACAGAAGAGCAAGUCCAAGCUGAUUUGCAGGCUCUCCACGACGGGUGCAGUAGACAUGACCAGUUUAUCGGCAGUCAACGACUUUUAUUCCCACAUCGUACUCGCAGCUGGCCGGAACAGGACCGUGGAAGUGUUUGACCUCAACGCCGGCUGCAGUGCAGCGGUGAUAGCGGAAGCCCACUCACGGCCUGUCCAUCAAAUCUGCCAAAAUAAAGGUUCAUCAUUUACAACCCAACAGCCUCAGGCUUAUAACCUUUUCCUGACCACGGCCAUUGGCGAUGGGAUGAGACUGUGGGACCUGAGAACCCUGAGGUGUGAGCGCCACUUUGAAGGGCAUCCAACCCGCGGCUAUCCAUGUGGAAUCGCUUUCAGUCCUUGUGGACGAUUCGCGGCUUGUGGGGCCGAGGACAGACACGCUUACGUGUAUGAAAUGGGCUCAAGCACGUUUUCUCACCGGCUGGCUGGGCACACAGACACUGUCACUGGAGUGGCCUUCAACCCAUCAGCGCCCCAGAUGAGGACAGCUCUGUGCCAGAGAAUGAGCUGGGAUCUGCCCUGACAAGUGGAGCCUCGUUUGAAAGUGUCGGUAACAGGCUCUGUGUCUGAACCAAAGUUUCCCUUGCAACCUGGUGUGGCUGCAUGAUGGAGUUUGGGCCGUGACAUAUGGUGGGUUUGACGUGUGCCACUCUUAGGGCCAACUUCUAAAGCCUCCAAGACACAGCCCCAUGCCCUGUGCCCUUCUGCAGCUCAGAGCAGAUGAGCCCAGUGACCUUGAGGCCCUUGAAGAUGGUGGAACCAGGAGACAUGAGGGGCCUUGGCCUGGAAACACAACUCGAAGGGAAAUCACUCAUCUGGAAAACGUGUUUGGACCCAUACCACACCGUGGCAAAUACCUGGUAAAACUGUCAUCUGAAAUUGCUUGGAAAUAGGACACUACCACCUAAACCCACAGCUCGUAGGCCAGGGCACCUCAACUGUAGUCCCCAGACCAGCAGCAUCGGUGUUACCUGGAAAAUUAAAAAUGCAAAGUUUUGGGCCCACUUCAGACCCCAGGUCAGAAAUUGUGGGUUGCAGAAAUCUGUGUUUUAAUAACCCUUCAGAUGACUGUGGUGCCCGACAAAGUUGAAAUGCCUGCUCCCAUGUGUGCUGGGUUUAGUUUGUGCUUUAGCAAAGCGGGAUAAGAAAGAAAGGAGGCCAGGAUGGAAUUCGCUGGUUUCCAACUAGAAGUGACAGAAAAUAGAAAGAGUCCAGUAAUGUGAGGUCUUGAAGUGUUGGGAGAAUUCAUUCAUCACUUCUAGAUUCCAGACAAUCAGAAAUAAAAUUUUAAAAGUCUUUCAAUGACAAACUAAGACUUCUCAGUUGGGAAAAAAAAAAAAAAAGGACUCAGUCUUGUUGCAGACAUGAGAUGAAGAGUGUGGUCUUUUCACAAAUGCCUGUGCAAGGGAGUCAAGGACAGAAGCCAUCCGGUGGGCUCCUUGGCACGGGGGCGGCUGAAGCAAACCAACCAGGAGCCCACGCAGCUGUCAAGGGCUUGUGUCAGCAAGUAAAGCCUAGACUGCUUGUGACUGUGAAGUGUAAAAGUGCCCCUGGGUCCUCAGGCCUGUGGACAGGACAAAGCCAAAGCCGCCCAGCGCCGUGUGAUGCGGCCACAGAGAACACGAGCCUCGGGAGAGAGGAGCCUGGGGCUGGAAAACAAGGGUGAAGGACGCUCCCCUCUGGCUGCAGGAGAGGGGCUGCUGAGGGCAAGAUCCAUCAUUUCUUGGGACCAAUGAUGCUGCUUCCUACUCUCUGCUUUCUGCCUGGGAGUUUUGUCUGGGACGCCUGUGUCUGCCCCACUCACUGUGUGGUGCAAGCUCCAUUUCCAGUGAGGACAACCGUGGCUGCCGAGAGCACCUUACAAGCCAGGCAUCCUCCUCUGAGCUCAAGGCAGCCUUGAGAAGUGGGACGAAGACUUCCUUCACGGGAAGAGGAGCGGCUCAGAGAAAGGAAGAGGCUAGUCCAGAACCACCACGUGGACAUCUUCUGUGAAGGCAAGGGCUCACCCUCACCCUGACGCCAGCCACCUGCCCCUCUUAAUAGGAGGGCGGGCCCUCCCCGCACAGCAGGCACUUCACUGCAGGCUCUGCUGCCUUUGGGAAAUGUGCCUCCCUUGUAGAGCUCUGUGGUGCAGAUUCGGCUAUCAAAGGAGUAGAACCCCCCCCUCCCCCCCGCCACCGUCCCACCCCCACAGAGCAGCUAAGAAAGCUGUUUGAUUUAACCCGUGGUUUCCCAAAUACUUUAGACCACUAAUUAAUUUUGUUUUCUGAAACAUUCGUUAAUAUGUUCACAGAAAAUUGUGGCAUUCACUUUGGAAAAUAUAUCUGUUUAAGAACAGAUAAUGAAUACAUAACAAAUUUAGAACUGUGUUAAGAUUCCAUAACUAAAACCACUCUAAACUUUCUGAAAUGGCUGAAAACGUUUCCCUAACUUUUCUGAAAGUACUUGCUGGGCUUCUUGGAGACUGAAUCAUCCCUUUUGAGCCCACUUAGGGGAAAGUUCAAAAGACCUCAGAGAAGACAAAAAGCAGGGCAAGAGAGACGGCCCAGUCUUCUAGCUCUCCACUGGAGAAAAUGCAUGUGGGAAAGGCUGGGGGUUUCCAUCCUCAAUAUUUAGUAAAAGAUAAAGUAAAAAUUACAACUGCCUUCUGAAUGGCUCCCCUCCCCUGACUUCAUGGGAGUGAUGACUCAGCCCUCUGUUUUGUAACUGCGGAGAUUGAAAGUGGAGACGGGACCUUUGGCAUUUCAGAAAAUGUCGACGCCGCUUUCUUCUGCUUUCUCCGGGACCCCUCUGGGGCCUCGCCUCCUCCCCUCCCGCUGAAAGCCUGCUGUGAAAGGAGCAAGGAUGUGAAAAAGAUGUACGACUCUUUGCUUCCUUAUGCUCGGCCCAAGUUUAUCAAAAGCUGUGGAGUUUGCUAAAAUAAUCCAGGGAAUUCGCCUGGAAAUGGUUUUUUUUUUUUUUUUUGGUUGUUGUUUGUCUUCACUUGUUCCAAAGAAGCAAAAUAAGACAGGGGCUGCCCCUUGUCCUGUCUCAUUCAUUUUUGACACCCUUGUUUCUCCACACAGGCCCUGGGGUGAAGGGCACAGGUGGGAUUCAGAAUAGAAAUGACUCGAGGGACGCAAGGAGUUGGGAUCAGAAGAAGCAGCAGAAACUCCUGCUCUGCAGACACAGCAGACAUUACUGGGAAAGACACCAGAGACCCAGGAGUUCACCCAAGUCCUCUGCACACUGUCUUCCCAGCCCUCUCUCCUGGAUCUGAGAUGAUUUCACUUAAAAACACAAGCCUUUGCUUAAAGGUAGAUGAACAUUCCUUUCAGUUUCUAAGAUGGGGGGCCCACGGUCCUAGGCGCUGAGUCAGAAACUUUUUAGAUGUCCCCAGAGUGCACAGGUUUAAGGACAGAGGGAGAUUCUCAGUCUUCCUGGGUCCUCCCUGUCUCUCAGCCCAGUCAUCACACUCUAAAUCCCAGGGACUUGACUCUGCCUUCCAAUAGUUCUCAGAUCCACCUACUUUGCUCCCUUCUUUCAGAGCGCAGGUAGCCACUUGCUCUCCCAGAGAGUGCUGCAGCGGUGAUGAUCGGUUUCCCCCCUCCCCACCUGCUCAGUCCUGCAAAGCCUGGACUCUGCUCCAAGGCCUUUGGGACCCAACACCUGCUUUCCAGCCUCAGGGCCUCAGGCCUGAGACCACAGGGGCUCUUCCCGGCGGCUGUACCUCCUGCCAUUCACCUGCUGAUUUCUUCCUCAUCUGUUUAUUCCUCUGAUCCAACAAGGUCAGGAUGGUAUGCAACCGCCACCCCCCCCCCACUGCCCCCACCACCACAGCACUGCCACGACCCUUGUCUGGGACGGAUGAUGUGGGGCUGCACUUCCUCUGUCGGCCCCCUGCCCUCGUCAGGAGGCCCAGCAUGUAGCAGGCAAGCAGCAGGCAGCAGGCAGGUGCUGAGUGGGUGUGGAAGGUGUGGCCCCUCACACCUCUGUGUCCUAUGCUCAGCGCUGUGCUUGGGCAUGGCGAGGCCUCAGCAGAUACUGUGCAGCACAGUGACACCAAUGGAACCCAGUAAAAAGACAGUUUCCAAUUUUCCUCGCUGCUGGGGCCCACCCAGAUCCUGGAGCAGAGCAUGGCCUGCAGGAAGCACAGGCUGGUGGACUGUGGCUGUGUCACGGCGAGCUUCCAGUGGCUCUCGCAGAACUCAAUUGGCACGGUAAAGGGACAAAUGAAGUUUCCAGCUUUUUUCUUUUAAUAGCUCAGAUAUCAAUUUUAUAGCUCUGAUGGACAUAAUUUAUAAAAUAAGUCUAUAUCUUACUGUAAAUUUGAGACGGUUAACCUUUAAUAAAGUUAAUAAGGGGCUUGUCAAAA